UUCCUCCCCCUCCCCGCCGAUUUUUUGAGGGGACCCGAAAAACGGAGUCCCUUUCCUUAGGCAACUUCCUCGGGCGCUGUGAGCACGGCCCUCCCCCUCACCGCCCCCACCCCCAACGCCUCGCAUCCCUUGGCCCGCUUCUCCACCUCGGGGCCACCGCCAGAAAAAUGCAUUCGAGAUCAUUCAGAGUGCACAGAAACAAAAAUAGAUUUUUAAUUGUUAGGUUAGGGGAAACUGAGAUGAGAAAUAAGAAUUUGGGGUGGGGGGGCGCGGCCGGGGCGAGUGCGUCCAGUUCUCCUUUUGGUUUUCCUAGAGCGUUGUUUGUGAUGUCUUUAUUGGUUUAGGGAGUCCGAGAGGCUCUAUGCUGGCUAUCUCGGUCGCGUGGAUUUUUGCGCAAGUUUUUAGAAAAACACUGACUCGAGUAGAGAGCAUUUCUCCGGAAAGUUUCAAGUGCAGCAAAAUAGCGAACGUGCAAAACUGGCCAAGGGGAGACCUCUAGUGGUUGAACGCGUCUUUUAAGUUCGGAAGGCCGAGAGCAAAGUUUGGCCUUUACUCGUAGCUACGUAGUCCGUUCAGACGUGGAAGUAAUUAGAGGACCUGAGCGAGCAGCCAGAUGUUGUGUGAAAGGAUGCUGAUCAGAAAUUGAAAGUUUAGUAAAUCGAAGCAAUGAAUUCUGAGGACUCAGACCCUGUAACUUCCAUCCGACAUGAGUUAUAUGGGAAAGACACUUUGCUUUUAUUCAGAGAUUUGAGAUUGAUCGCUCCCUGAAUUGGAAACAAUUGUUUGCUUUUGCAUUUAUCGGUGUCUGUACCUCUGAUCAAUUUUUAAUUAACGAGUCUCAGCUGAUGACUUUAUUUUGAAUGUUAAGAAAACUGCUAAGUUGAAAUGUGUUUAAAACUUUGAAGAAAUGGAAAAGACCUUUAGUUGAGAUUUGUCUUUUAUAUGAGCUGUUCAUUUUACUGUCUGAUAAGUGUAAGGCAAUUUUAUAUAGUUUCUUAGCUGUAUAGUUAUGUAUAGUCCGAGUAAGUAGUCCCUUUUGGUUCUAAGACUGUAAUUUUGUUUCACUGAGUACGAAAUUAUUUCUGAAUACUUGUAUAAUUUGUGAUUUAAAGUCCUUAAAUACAUGGGCAAAAAUUUUAUGUAAUAUCUAUUCUUUUUCCAGUGUGUUUUCUGUAAAAUAUCUUUAAUUUUAAAGAUAAAAGCAGUGAGGGAAAUUAAAGUUGACUCAAAUGAUCCUUGUAACUUUCACCUGCCUGUCAUAUACAACAGGAGAGACGUUAUUGGGUGAAUUUAGGACAUGGGAAUGAUACGAAUGAUUAAAAUCCAUUUCAACUCAUCUAGAACCAGCUUAUUUUAUUUUAAUUUACCGAGUGGCAUGGUGUAAAAUUAUGCCUAAGUGAUUCAGAAUAACCCUUAGGAGAAAUCUUGAGAGUGGACAGCAAUUGUGAAGAUCGCCAGAGAGUUCUGUGUUUCAUCACCGCCGAAAGGUUAAAAAAUAAAUCAUGACUGAAUCUGCCUCUAGCACAAGUGGUCAAGAGUUUGAUGUGUUCAGUGUUAUGGACUGGAAAGAUGGAGUGGGCACGUUACCAGGAAGUGACUUAAAGUUUCGGGUAAAUGAGUUUGGAGCCCUGGAAGUUAUUACAGAUGAGAAUGAGAUGGAAAAUGUUAAAAAAGCAACUGCUACCACCACUUGGAUGGUACCAACUGCUCAAGAAGCCUACACAGGUGAUUUAGCCAAAAGCCUGCCACUUUUUUUCUCAUCUACUCCGAUGGUUGUAACUAACACCUAUAUGCUGAUGACUCCUAAAUCUACAUCUCCAGCCCCGACCUCUCCCCCGAGCUCCAGGCCCGUAUUUCCACCUGCCUACUGGACAUCUCCACCUGGAUGUCCCACAGUCUUUUCAGAGAAGACUGGGAUGCCUUUCAGGUUGAAGGAUCCAGUGAAAGUAGAAGGGCUUCAGUUCUGUGAGAACUGUUGUCAGUAUGGCAACGUAGAUGAGUGUCUUUCUGGAGGAAACUAUUGCAGCCAGAAUUGUGCUCGGCACAUCAAAGAUAAAGAUCAGAAGGAAGAAAGGGACGUAGAAGAAGACAAUGAGGAAGAAGAUCCUAAGUGUAGUCGGAAGAAAAAACCAAAAUUAUCUCUGAAAGCUGACACCAAGGAGGAUGGAGAAGAGAGAGAUGAUGAAAUGGAGAACAAACAAGAUGUAAGAAUCCUGAGGGGUUCGCAGAGAGCACGGAGGAAAAGACGAGGGGAUUCGGCUGUACUAAAGCAGGGUUUGCCUCCUAAAGGAAAGAAAGCGUGGUGCUGGGCAUCCUACCUGGAAGAGGAGAAAGCGGUGGCAGUGCCGGCGAAGCUGUUCAAGGAGCAUCAAUCCUUUCCAUAUAACAAAAAUGGAUUCAAAGUUGGCAUGAAAUUAGAAGGCGUGGAUCCUGAGCAUCAGUCUGUGUACUGUGUCCUCACCGUCGCGGAGGUUUGUGGAUACCGGAUAAAGCUUCACUUUGAUGGGUAUUCUGAUUGCUAUGACUUCUGGGUGAAUGCAGACGCUCUGGAUAUCCACCCAGUUGGGUGGUGUGAGAAAACCGGCCACAAACUCCAUCCUCCAAAAGGGUAUAAAGAAGAAGAAUUCAAUUGGCAGACCUAUCUUAAGACAUGUAAAGCUCAAGCUGCUCCUAAGUCAUUAUUUGAAAAUCAGAAUAUAACAGUGAUCCCAUCGGGCUUUCGAGUUGGUAUGAAGCUUGAGGCAGUAGACAAAAAGAAUCCCUCAUUCAUCUGUGUUGCUACGGUAACAGAUAUGGUGGACAAUCGUUUCCUGGUACAUUUUGACAACUGGGAUGAGAGCUAUGACUAUUGGUGUGAAGCAUCAAGUCCACAUAUUCAUCCAGUUGGUUGGUGUAAGGAACAUAGAAGAACCCUUAUUACUCCACCAGGUUAUCCAAAUGUGAAACAUUUUUCUUGGGAUAAAUACUUAGAAGAAACCAAUUCUUUACCUGCUCCUGCAAGAGCUUUCAAAGUGAAACCUCCUCAUGGAUUCCAGAAAAAAAUGAAGCUUGAGGUUGUAGACAAAAGGAACCCUAUGUUUAUUAGAGUAGCAACUGUGGCAGACACAGAUGAUCACCGGGUAAAAGUUCACUUUGAUGGCUGGAACAAUUGCUAUGAUUACUGGAUAGAUGCAGAUUCUCCUGAUAUUCACCCUGUAGGCUGGUGUUCAAAAACAGGACAUCCCCUUCAGCCUCCUUUGAGCCCCUUAGAAUUAAUGGAAGCUUCAGAACAUGGUGGAUGCUCAACCCCGGGAUGUAAAGGGAUUGGCCAUUUCAAGAGAGCGAGACAUCUGGGCCCUCACAGUGCUGCCAACUGUCCCUAUUCAGAAAUCAAUUUGAAUAAAGACCGUAUUUUUCCAGACCGCUUAAGUGGUGAGAUGCCUCCGGCUAGUCCGUCAUUUCCAAGAAAUAAAAGGACAGAUGCAAAUGAAAGCUCUUCUUCCCCUGAAAUCAGAGACCAGCAUGCUGAUGAUGUCAAAGAAGACUUUGAAGAGAGAACAGAAAGUGAAAUGAGAACAUCACAUGAAGCCAGAGGUGCCCGGGAAGAACCCACCGUCCAGCAGGCACAGCGUCGGUCAGCUGUCUUUCUGUCCUUUAAGUCCCCAAUUCCAUGUCUGCCCUUGCGCUGGGAGCAGCAAAGCAAACUUCUUCCAACUGUCGCAGGAAUCCCUGCCAGUAAAGUUUCCAAAUGGAGCACAGACGAGGUGUCAGAAUUUAUACAGAGCUUACCUGGGUGUGAAGAACAUGGAAAGGUAUUUAAAGAUGAACAAAUUGAUGGAGAAGCAUUUCUACUUAUGACUCAAACAGACAUUGUUAAAAUUAUGAGCAUUAAACUGGGCCCUGCUCUCAAAAUUUUCAAUUCCAUCCUGAUGUUCAAAGCUGCAGAGAAGAAUUCUCACAAUGAACUUUGAAGAUGGUGAAUUCUGAAUACCAUCAGCAUUCUGCUUUAAAGCUCAUGUUUUAUUCAAAGCACAAGGACGGUUAUAACUCCUAAGUGAGAAGUCUCCAAAACUCAAAAGAGCAACACUAUCGGAUUAUUUAUAUUACUCAAGAGACAAUAUAUAUGAAUUCUUAUGAAAGUGCUUGAGCUUUUAACCAGGUACUGUCUAACAACAGUCAUCUUUUGGUUCUGUUCACUGAGCUAAAUUUAUCUUUGUAAAUCUUUUUGAGUCUGGGGGGUGGGGGGAAGGGGGGCUUCAUUAAUUAUUUAUGGUAAUGGGGGGCAGAGUAAGAACUUUUGGCAUUUUGUAAACAUUGUUGAAUUCUCUUUCAUGUACACUGUUUCUUUUUCAAUACUUUCAGAAACCUUUUUAUAUAAUCAAAUUUCAAUUUAAACCAAAUUAGUCGAAACCUGGCUAAGUUUAGCCAGUAGGACUGUUAUCUGUAUUGUUAAUUUUGUGCCAUAUUUUGAAUUGCAACAUUAUGCUAAGUAUAACUUUGCAAGUCAUGAUAUUGCCUAACUGCUUGUCAUAAUUGUCAGGGCUGAAUAGUUGUAAGAAUGACUUUUCUUUGAAUCAGUAUUUUUCCUUUUGCACGCAUUAUGAAAUGUUAAACAAAUUACUUUUCACCAGCAUCUUUACUAUAAUUACCAAAAACAUGUAUAUAAAAGAAUGAAAUUGAAAAAUAAAAUAUAUAAACAUAAAUAAAUUAGGUAGUGUAUUUUGAGUGGCAUCAGUCUCACUCAUCUUGGUGCCCCGGUGUUUACAAGAGCCAGAUGGUGUCAGAGGAGUACGCAGUUGUAUGCAGUUAUGGUUGGGGGGAAUGUUUGUGAGGGUCUUGAACUAUUUAUGAGAUGAUCUUGAGCUUCUAAUUUUCAUUGAUGAAAUUGUGGUGGUUUACAGAGACUAAGAGCUCAUUCUGUCAACAGAAACACUAAUCUGUACAGAGCGCUGUCUCAGGUCAUGCAUUGUCCUCCAAACCCAAAGGUUUUUUUCAGGGUUGGCUAGAGAGCGAGUAUUGUGAUUUUGCUGAAAAGACAAGGUGUGAAGGAGCAACUUCAGUUGACACAAAAUUUGAAAUGCUCACAGAUCAGGGAGGUGAUUUCCCAAAGUAAUUGCCCAAGAACCUCCGUUUUGGAAGGAUUCCUUUUUCUGUAGAAUACUUUGCCUCGAUAUAUAAGCAUACAGAUGCACUUUAAAUGAAAACCCUUGAUUAUAAAUUGAUAGCUGGUAGUGUUUCUUUUGCAAGAAUGCAUUUCUAAGGCAAAAGGUAAAUUAUUUUGUCCGUCUUUUGAUGUACUUUCUGAUUCCAGGAUUGGAUAUUUAUUCAAGGACUAUUUUAAAAAUAGAAAGUAAGUUUGUAGCAUGCUGUCUGAAUUCUGGGGUAAGUUCCACCUCUUCUUUAGUUGCUUUCGUUUUUUAUGAUGUAGGACUUCCUUUGAUAUCCCUGUUGGAAGUCCAUUAGCAGUCCUUUGCAUUUGCCAAUUCAAGGUAAAACAGGGUCAGUGACAUCUGCAGUGUCCCAGUCAUUUAUUUGCAUGAAUCUGCUUAAAUAAGUUUUUUGUUGCUGUUUUUUCUUUUUUAUGUUUUGUUCAGAAUUUGUACAUUCAAGUUGUACUUGUUAUAUCUGACAUGAAUGAAAUAAAAUCUUAAUUACA